AGAAGUGCUCCUGCCCCGGGAAGAGGCUCAGUGCAGAAGGAGGAAGGACAGCACAGCUGACAGCCGUGCUCAGGAAGAUUCUGGAUCCUAGGCUCAUCUCCACAGAGGAGAACACGCAGGGAGCAGAGACCAUGGGGCCCCUCUCAGCCCCUCCCUGCACACAGCAUAUAACCUGGAAAGGGCUCCUGCUCACAGCAUCACUUUUAAACUUCUGGAACCCGCCCACCACAGCCCAAGUCACGAUUGAAGCCCAGCCACCAAAAGUUUCCGAGGGGAAGGAUGUUCUUCUACUUGUCCACAAUUUGCCCCAGAAUCUUACUGGCUACAUCUGGUACAAAGGACAAAUCAGGGACCUCUACCAUUAUGUUACAUCAUAUAUAGUAGACGGUCAAAUAAUUAAAUAUGGGCCUGCAUACAGUGGACGAGAAACAGUAUAUUCCAAUGCAUCCCUGCUGAUCCAGAAUGUCACCCAGGAAGACACAGGAUCCUACACUUUACACAUCAUAAAGCGAGGUGAUGGGACUGGAGGAGUAACUGGACGUUUCACCUUCACCUUAUACCUGGAGACUCCCAAACCCUCCAUCUCCAGCAGCAAUUUCAACCCCAGGGAGGCCACGGAGGCUGUGAUUUUAACCUGUGAUCCUGAGACUCCAGAUGCAAGCUACCUGUGGUGGAUGAAUGGUCAGAGCCUCCCUAUGACUCACAGCUUGCAGCUGUCUGAAACCAACAGGACCCUCUACCUAUUUGGUGUCACAAACUAUACUGCAGGACCCUAUGAAUGUGAAAUACGGAACCCAGUGAGUGCCAGCCGCAGUGACCCAGUCACCCUGAAUCUCCUCCCGAAGCUGCCCAAGCCCUACAUCACCAUCAAUAACUUAAACCCCAGGGAGAAUAAGGAUGUCUCAACCUUCACCUGUGAACCUAAGAGUGAGAACUACACCUACAUUUGGUGGCUAAAUGGUCAGAGCCUCCCGGUCAGUCCCAGGGUAAAGCGACGCAUUGAAAACAGGAUCCUCAUUCUACCCAGUGUCACGAGAAAUGAAACAGGACCCUAUCAAUGUGAAAUACGGGACCGAUAUGGUGGCAUCCGCAGUGACCCAGUCACCCUGAAUGUCCUCUAUGGUCCAGACCUCCCCAGAAUUUACCCUUCAUUCACCUAUUACCAUUCAGGACAAAACCUCUACUUGUCCUGCUUUGCGGACUCUAACCCACCGGCACAGUAUUCUUGGACAAUUAAUGGGAAGUUUCAGCUAUCAGGACAAAAGCUUUCUAUCCCCCAGAUUACUACAAAGCAUAGCGGGCUCUAUGCUUGCUCUGUUCGUAACUCAGCCACUGGCAAGGAAAGCUCCAAAUCCGUGACAGUCAGAGUCUCUGACUGGACAUUACCCUGAAUUCUACUAGUUCCUCCAAUUCCAUCUUCUCCCAUGGAACCUCAAAGAGCAAGACCCACUCUGUUCCAGAAGCCCUAUAAGUCAGAGUUGGACAACUCAAUGUAAAUUUCAUGGGAAAAUCCUUGUACCUGAUGUCUGAGCCACUCAGAACUCACCAAAAUGUUCAACACCAUAACAACAGCUGCUCAAACUGUAAACAAGGAAAACAAGUUGAUGACUUCACACUGUGGACAGCUUUUCCCAAGAUGUCAGAAUAAGACUCCCCAUCAUGAUGAGGCUCUCACCCCUCUUAGCUGUCCUUGCUUGUGCCUGCCUCUUUCACUUGGCAGGAUAAUGCAGUCAUUAGAAUUUCACAUGUAGUAUAGGAGCUUCUGAGGGUAACAACAGAGUGUCAGAUAUGUCAUCUCAACCUCAGACUUUUACAUAACAUCUCAGGAGGAAAUGUGGCUCUCUCCAUCUUGCAUACAGGGCUCCCAAUAGAAAUGAACACAGAGAUAUUGCCUGUGUGUUUGCAGAGAAGAUGGUUUCUAUAAAGAGUAGGAAAGCUGAAAUUAUAGUAGACUCCCCUUUAAAUGCACAUUGUGUGGAUGGCUCUCACCAUUUCCUAAGAGAUACAUUGUAAAACGUGACAGUAAGACUGAUUCUAGCAGAAUAAAACAUGUACUACAUUUGCUAA